GGUGCGCGCGCCCGCGCCGAUGUGUGUGAGUGCGUGUCCUGCUCGCUCCAUGUUGCCGCCUCUCCCGGUACCUGCUGCUGCUCCCGGGGCUGCGGGAAAUGCGAGAGGCUGAGCCGGGGAGGAGGAACCCGAGCAGCAGCGGCGGCGGCGGCGGCCGCGGCGGCGGGAGCCCCCCAGGAGGAGGACCGGGAUCCAUGUGUCUUUCCUGGUGACUAGGAUGUCGUCGGAGGAGGACAAGAGCGUGGAGCAGCCGCAGCCGCCGCCACCACCCCCCGAGGAGCCUGGAGCCCCGGCCCCGAGCCCCGCAGCCGCAGACAAAAGACCUCGGGGCCGGCCUCGCAAAGAUGGCGCUUCCCCUUUCCAGAGAGCCAGAAAGAAACCUCGAAGUAGGGGGAAAACUGCAGUGGAAGAUGAGGACAGCAUGGAUGGGCUGGAGACAACAGAAACAGAAACGAUUGUGGAAACAGAAAUCAAAGAACAAUCUGCAGAAGAGGAUGCUGAAGCAGAAGUGGAUAACAGCAAACAGCUAAUUCCAACUCUUCAGCGAUCUGUGUCUGAGGAAUCGGCAAACUCCCUGGUCUCUGUUGGUGUAGAAGCCAAAAUCAGUGAACAGCUCUGCGCUUUUUGUUACUGUGGGGAAAAAAGUUCCUUAGGACAAGGAGACUUAAAACAAUUCAGAAUAACGCCUGGAUUUAUCUUGCCAUGGAGAAACCAACCUUCUAACAAGAAGGACAUUGAUGACAACAGCAAUGGAACCUAUGAGAAAAUGCAAAACUCAGCACCACGAAAACAAAGAGGACAGAGAAAAGAACGAUCUCCUCAGCAGAAUAUAGUAUCUUGUGUAAGUGUAAGCACCCAGACAGCUUCAGAUGAUCAAGCUGGUAAACUGUGGGAUGAACUCAGUCUGGUUGGGCUUCCAGAUGCCAUUGAUAUCCAAGCCUUAUUUGAUUCUACAGGCACUUGUUGGGCUCAUCACCGUUGUGUGGAGUGGUCACUAGGAGUAUGCCAGAUGGAAGAACCAUUGUUAGUGAACGUGGACAAAGCUGUUGUCUCAGGGAGCACAGAACGAUGUGCAUUUUGUAAGCACCUUGGAGCCACUAUCAAAUGCUGUGAAGAGAAAUGUACCCAGAUGUAUCAUUAUCCUUGUGCUGCAGGAGCCGGCACCUUUCAGGAUUUCAGUCACAUCUUCCUGCUUUGUCCAGAACACAUUGACCAAGCUCCUGAAAGAUCGAAGGAAGAUGCAAACUGUGCAGUGUGCGACAGCCCGGGAGACCUCUUAGAUCAGUUCUUUUGUACUACUUGUGGUCAGCACUAUCAUGGAAUGUGCCUGGAUAUAGCGGUUACUCCAUUAAAACGUGCAGGUUGGCAAUGUCCUGAGUGCAAAGUGUGCCAGAACUGCAAACAAUCGGGAGAAGAUAGCAAGAUGCUAGUGUGUGAUACGUGUGACAAAGGGUAUCAUACUUUUUGUCUUCAACCAGUUAUGAAAUCAGUACCAACCAAUGGCUGGAAAUGCAAAAAUUGCAGAAUAUGUAUAGAGUGUGGCACACGGUCUAGUUCUCAGUGGCACCACAAUUGCCUGAUAUGUGACAAUUGUUACCAACAGCAGGAUAACUUAUGUCCCUUCUGUGGGAAGUGUUAUCAUCCAGAAUUGCAGAAAGACAUGCUUCAUUGUAAUAUGUGCAAAAGGUGGGUUCACCUAGAGUGUGACAAACCAACAGAUCAUGAACUGGAUACUCAGCUCAAAGAAGAGUAUAUCUGCAUGUAUUGUAAACACCUGGGAGCUGAGAUGGAUCGUUUACAGCCAGGUGAGGAAGUGGAGAUAGCUGAGCUCACUACAGAUUAUAACAAUGAAAUGGAAGUUGAAGGCCCUGAAGAUCAAAUGGUAUUCUCAGAGCAGGCAGCUAAUAAAGAUGUCAACGGUCAGGAGUCCACUCCUGGAAUUGUUCCAGAUGCGGUUCAAGUCCACACUGAAGAGCAACAGAAGAGUCAUCCCUCAGAAAGUCUUGACACAGAUAGUCUUCUUAUUGCUGUAUCAUCCCAACAUACAGUGAAUACUGAAUUGGAAAAACAGAUUUCUAAUGAAGUUGAUAGUGAAGACCUGAAAAUGUCUUCUGAAGUGAAGCAUAUUUGUGGCGAAGAUCAAAUUGAAGAUAAAAUGGAAGUGACAGAAAACAUUGAAGUCGUUACACACCAGAUCACUGUGCAGCAAGAACAACUGCAGUUGUUAGAGGAACCUGAAACAGUGGUAUCCAGAGAAGAAUCAAGGCCUCCAAAAUUAGUCAUGGAAUCUGUCACUCUUCCACUAGAAACCUUAGUGUCCCCACAUGAGGAAAGUAUUUCAUUAUGUCCUGAGGAACAGUUGGUUAUAGAAAGGCUACAAGGAGAAAAGGAACAGAAAGAAAAUUCUGAACUUUCUACUGGAUUGAUGGACUCUGAAAUGACUCCUACAAUUGAGGGUUGUGUGAAAGAUGUUUCAUACCAAGGAGGCAAAUCUAUAAAGUUAUCAUCUGAGACAGAGUCAUCAUUUUCAUCAUCAGCAGACAUAAGCAAGGCAGAUGUGUCUUCCUCCCCAACACCUUCUUCAGACUUGCCUUCGCAUGACAUGCUGCAUAAUUACCCUUCAGCUCUUAGUUCCUCUGCUGGAAACAUCAUGCCAACAACUUACAUCUCAGUCACUCCAAAAAUUGGCAUGGGUAAACCAGCUAUUACUAAGAGAAAAUUUUCUCCUGGUAGACCUCGGUCCAAACAGGGGGCUUGGAGUACCCAUAAUACAGUGAGCCCACCUUCCUGGUCCCCAGACAUUUCAGAAGGUCGGGAAAUUUUUAAACCCAGGCAGCUUCCUGGCAGUGCCAUUUGGAGCAUCAAAGUGGGCCGUGGGUCUGGAUUUCCAGGAAAGCGGAGACCUCGAGGUGCAGGACUGUCGGGGCGAGGUGGCCGAGGCAGGUCAAAGCUGAAAAGUGGAAUCGGAGCUGUUGUAUUACCUGGGGUGUCUACUGCAGAUAUUUCAUCAAAUAAGGAUGAUGAAGAAAACUCUAUGCACAAUACAGUUGUGUUGUUUUCUAGCAGUGACAAGUUCACUUUGAAUCAGGAUAUGUGUGUAGUUUGUGGCAGUUUUGGCCAAGGAGCAGAAGGAAGAUUACUUGCCUGUUCUCAGUGUGGUCAGUGUUACCAUCCAUACUGUGUCAGUAUUAAGAUCACUAAAGUGGUUCUUAGCAAAGGUUGGAGGUGUCUUGAGUGCACUGUGUGUGAGGCCUGUGGGAAGGCAACUGACCCAGGAAGACUCCUGCUGUGUGAUGACUGUGACAUAAGUUAUCACACCUACUGCCUAGACCCUCCAUUGCAGACAGUUCCCAAAGGAGGCUGGAAGUGCAAAUGGUGUGUUUGGUGCAGACACUGUGGAGCAACAUCUGCAGGUCUAAGAUGUGAAUGGCAGAACAAUUACACACAGUGCGCUCCUUGUGCAAGCUUAUCUUCCUGUCCAGUCUGCUAUCGAAACUAUAGAGAAGAAGAUCUUAUUCUGCAAUGUAGACAAUGUGAUAGAUGGAUGCAUGCAGUUUGUCAGAACUUAAAUACUGAGGAAGAAGUGGAAAAUGUAGCAGACAUUGGUUUUGAUUGUAGCAUGUGCAGACCCUAUAUGCCUGCGUCUAAUGUGCCUUCCUCAGACUGCUGUGAAUCUUCACUUGUAGCACAAAUUGUCACAAAAGUAAAAGAGCUAGACCCACCCAAGACUUAUACCCAGGAUGGUGUGUGUUUGACUGAAUCAGGGAUGACUCAGUUACAGAGCCUCACAGUUACAGUUCCAAGAAGAAAACGGUCAAAACCAAAAUUGAAAUUGAAGAUUAUAAAUCAGAAUAGCGUGGCCGUCCUUCAGACCCCUCCAGACAUCCAAUCAGAGCAUUCAAGGGAUGGUGAAAUGGAUGAUAGUCGAGAAGGAGAACUUAUGGAUUGUGAUGGAAAAUCAGAAUCUAGUCCUGAGCGGGAAGCUGUGGAUGAUGAAACUAAGGGAGUGGAAGGAACAGAUGGUGUCAAAAAGAGAAAAAGGAAACCAUACAGACCAGGUAUUGGUGGAUUUAUGGUGCGGCAAAGAAGUCGAACUGGGCAAGGGAAAACCAAAAGAUCUGUGAUCAGAAAAGAUUCCUCAGGCUCUAUUUCCGAGCAGUUACCUUGCAGAGAUGAUGGCUGGAGUGAGCAGUUACCAGAUACUUUAGUUGAUGAAUCUGUUUCUGUUACUGAAAGCACUGAAAAAAUAAAGAAGAGAUACCGAAAAAGGAAAAAUAAGCUUGAAGAAACUUUCCCUGCCUAUUUACAAGAAGCUUUCUUUGGAAAAGAUCUUCUAGAUACAAGUAGACAAAGCAAGAUAAGUUUAGAUAAUCUGUCAGAAGAUGGAGCUCAGCUUUUAUAUAAAACAAACAUGAACACAGGUUUCUUGGAUCCUUCCUUAGAUCCACUACUUAGUUCAUCCUCGGCUCCAACAAAAUCUGGAACUCACGGUCCUGCUGAUGACCCAUUAGCUGAUAUUUCUGAAGUUUUAAACACAGAUGAUGACAUUCUUGGAAUAAUUUCAGAUGAUCUAGCAAAAUCAGUUGAUCAUUCAGAUAUUGGUCCUGUCACUGAUGAUCCUUCCUCUUUGCCUCAGCCAAAUGUCAAUCAGAGUUCACGACCAUUAAGUGAAGAACAGCUAGAUGGGAUCCUCAGUCCUGAACUAGACAAAAUGGUCACAGAUGGAGCAAUUCUUGGAAAAUUAUAUAAAAUUCCAGAGCUUGGCGGAAAAGAUGUUGAAGACUUAUUUACAGCUGUACUUAGUCCUGCGAACACUCAGCCAACUCCAUUGCCACAGCCUCCCCCACCAACACAGCUGUUGCCAAUACACAAUCAGGAUGCUUUUUCACGGAUGCCUCUCAUGAAUGGCCUUAUUGGAUCCAGUCCUCAUCUCCCACAUAAUUCUUUGCCACCUGGAAGCGGACUGGGAACUUUCUCUGCAAUUGCACAAUCCUCUUAUCCUGAUGCCAGGGAUAAAAAUUCAGCCUUUAAUCCAAUGGCAAGUGAUCCUAACAACUCUUGGACAUCAUCAGCUCCCACUGUGGAAGGAGAAAAUGACACAAUGUCGAAUGCCCAGAGAAGCACGCUUAAGUGGGAGAAAGAGGAGGCUCUGGGUGAAAUGGCAACUGUUGCCCCAGUUCUCUACACCAAUAUUAAUUUCCCCAACUUAAAGGAAGAAUUCCCUGAUUGGACUACUAGAGUGAAGCAAAUUGCCAAAUUGUGGAGAAAAGCAAGCUCACAAGAAAGAGCACCAUAUGUGCAAAAAGCCAGAGAUAACAGAGCUGCUUUACGCAUUAAUAAAGUACAGAUGUCAAAUGAUUCCAUGAAAAGGCAGCAACAGCAAGAUAGCAUUGAUCCCAGCUCUCGUAUUGAUUCGGAGCUUUUUAAAGAUCCUUUAAAGCAAAGAGAAUCAGAACAUGAACAGGAAUGGAAAUUUAGACAGCAAAUGCGUCAGAAAAGUAAGCAGCAAGCUAAAAUUGAAGCCACACAGAAACUUGAACAGGUGAAAAAUGAGCAGCAGCAGCAGCAACAACAGCAAUUUGGUUCUCAGCAUCUUCUGGUGCAGUCUGGUUCAGAUACACCAAGUAGUGGGAUACAGAGUCCCUUGACACCUCAGCCUGGCAAUGGAAAUAUGUCUCCUGCACAGUCAUUCCAUAAAGAACUGUUUACAAAACAGCCACCCAGUACCCCUACGUCUACAUCUUCAGAUGAUGUGUUUGUAAAGCCACAAGCUCCACCUCCUCCUCCAGCCCCAUCCCGGAUUCCCAUCCAGGAUAGUCUUUCUCAGGCUCAGACUUCUCAGCCACCCUCACCGCAAGUGUUUUCACCUGGGUCCUCUAACUCACGACCACCAUCUCCAAUGGAUCCAUAUGCAAAAAUGGUUGGUACCCCUCGACCACCUCCUGUGGGCCAUAGUUUUUCCAGAAGAAAUUCUGCUGCACCAGUGGAAAACUGUACACCUUUAUCAUCGGUAUCUAGGCCCCUUCAAAUGAAUGAGACAACAGCAAAUAGGCCAUCCCCUGUCAGAGAUUUAUGUUCUUCUUCCACGACAAAUAAUGACCCCUAUGCAAAACCUCCAGACACACCUAGGCCUGUGAUGACAGAUCAAUUUCCCAAAUCCUUGGGCCUAUCCCGGUCUCCUGUAGUUUCAGAACAAACUGCAAAAGGCCCUAUAGCAGCUGGAACCAGUGAUCACUUUACUAAACCAUCUCCUAGGGCAGAUGUGUUUCAAAGACAAAGGAUACCUGACUCAUAUGCACGACCCUUGUUGACACCUGCACCUCUUGAUAGUGGUCCUGGACCUUUUAAGACUCCAAUGCAACCUCCUCCAUCCUCUCAGGAUCCUUAUGGAUCAGUGUCACAGGCAUCAAGGCGAUUGUCUGUUGACCCUUAUGAAAGGCCUGCUUUGACACCAAGACCUAUAGAUAAUUUUUCUCAUAAUCAGUCAAAUGAUCCAUAUAGUCAGCCUCCCCUUACCCCACAUCCAGCAGUGAAUGAAUCUUUUGCCCAUCCUUCAAGGGCUUUUUCCCAGCCUGGAACCAUAUCAAGGCCAACAUCUCAGGACCCAUACUCCCAACCCCCAGGAACUCCACGACCUGUUGUAGAUUCUUAUUCCCAAUCUUCAGGAACAGCUAGGUCCAAUACAGACCCUUACUCUCAACCUCCUGGAACUCCCCGGCCUACUACUGUUGACCCAUAUAGUCAGCAGCCCCAAACCCCAAGACCAUCUACACAAACUGACUUGUUUGUUACACCUGUAACAAAUCAGAGGCAUUCUGAUCCAUAUGCUCAUCCUCCUGGAACACCAAGACCUGGAAUUUCUGUCCCUUACUCUCAGCCACCAGCAACACCAAGGCCAAGGAUUUCAGAGGGUUUUACUAGGUCCUCAAUGACAAGACCAGUCCUCAUGCCAAAUCAGGAUCCUUUCCUGCAAGCAGCACAAAACCGAGGACCAGCUUUACCUGGCCCGUUGGUAAGGCCACCUGAUACAUGUUCCCAGACACCUAGGCCCCCUGGACCUGGUCUUUCAGACACAUUUAGCCGUGUUUCCCCAUCUGCUGCCCGUGAUCCCUAUGAUCAGUCUCCAAUGACUCCAAGAUCUCAGUCUGACUCUUUUGGAACAAGUCAAACUGCCCAUGAUGUUGCUGAUCAGCCAAGGCCUGGAUCAGAGGGGAGCUUCUGUGCAUCUUCAAACUCUCCAAUGCACUCCCAAGGCCAGCAGUUCUCUGGUGUCUCCCAACUUCCUGGACCUGUGCCAACUUCAGGAGUAACUGAUACACAGAAUACUGUAAAUAUGGCCCAAGCAGAUACAGAGAAAUUGAGACAGCGGCAGAAGUUACGUGAAAUCAUUCUCCAGCAGCAACAGCAGAAGAAGAUUGCAGGUCGACAGGAGAAGGGGUCACAGGACUCACCCGCAGUGCCUCAUCCAGGGCCUCUUCAACACUGGCAACCAGAGAAUGUUAACCAGGCUUUCACCAGACCCCCACCUCCCUAUCCUGGGAACAUUAGGUCUCCUGUUGCCCCUCCUUUAGGACCUAGAUAUGCUGUUUUCCCAAAAGAUCAGCGUGGACCCUAUCCUCCUGAUGUUGCUAGUAUGGGGAUGAGACCUCAUGGAUUUAGAUUUGGAUUUCCAGGAGGUAGUCAUGGUACCAUGCCGAGUCAAGAGCGCUUCCUUGUGCCUCCUCAGCAAAUACAGGGAUCUGGAGUUUCUCCACAGCUAAGAAGAUCAGUAUCUGUAGAUAUGCCUAGGCCUUUAAAUAACUCACAAAUGAAUAAUCCAGUUGGACUUCCUCAGCAUUUUUCACCACAGAGCUUGCCAGUUCAGCAGCACAACAUACUGGGCCAAGCAUAUAUUGAACUGAGACAUAGGGCUCCUGACGGAAGGCAACGGCUGCCUUUCAGUGCUCCACCUGGCAGCGUUGUAGAGGCAUCUUCUAAUCUGAGACAUGGAAACUUCAUUCCCCGGCCAGACUUUCCGGGCCCUAGACACACAGACCCCAUGCGACGACCUCCCCAGGGUCUACCUAAUCAGCUACCUGUGCACCCAGAUUUGGAACAAGUGCCACCAUCUCAACAAGAGCAAGGUCAUUCUGUCCAUUCAUCUUCUAUGGUCAUGAGGACUCUGAACCAUCCACUAGGUGGUGAAUUUUCAGAAGCUCCUUUGUCAACAUCUGUACCGUCUGAAACAACGUCUGAUAAUUUACAGAUAACCACCCAGCCUUCUGAUGGUCUAGAGGAAAAACUUGAUUCUGAUGACCCUUCUGUGAAGGAACUGGAUGUUAAAGACCUUGAGGGGGUUGAAGUCAAAGACUUAGAUGAUGAAGAUCUUGAAAACUUAAAUUUAGAUACAGAGGAUGGCAAGGUAGUUGAAUUGGAUACUUUAGAUAAUUUGGAAACUAAUGAUCCCAACCUGGAUGACCUCUUAAGGUCAGGAGAGUUUGAUAUCAUUGCAUAUACAGAUCCAGAACUUGACAUGGGAGAUAAGAAAAGCAUGUUUAAUGAGGAACUAGACCUUCCAAUUGAUGAUAAGUUAGAUAAUCAGUGUGUAUCUGUUGAACCAAAAAAAAAGGAACAAGAAAACAAAACUCUGGUUCUCUCUGAUAAACAUUCACCACAGAAAAAAUCCACUGUUACCAAUGAGGUAAAAACGGAAGUACUGUCUCCAAAUUCUAAGGUGGAAUCCAAAUGUGAAACUGAAAAAAAUGAUGAGAAUAAAGAUAAUGUUGACACUCCUUGCUCACAGGCUUCUGCUCACUCAGACCUAAAUGAUGGAGAAAAGACUUCUUUGCAUCCUUGUGAUCCAGAUCUAUUUGAGAAAAGAACCAAUCGAGAAACUGCUGGCCCCAGUGCAAAUGUCAUUCAGGCAUCCACUCAACUACCUGCUCAAGAUGUAAUAAACUCUUGUGGCAUAACUGGAUCAACUCCAGUUCUCUCAAGUUUACUUGCUAAUGAGAAAUCUGAUAAUUCAGACAUUAGGCCAUCGGGGUCUCCACCACCACCAACUCUGCCGGCCUCCCCAUCCAAUCAUGUGUCAAGUUUGCCUCCUUUCAUAGCACCGCCUGGCCGUGUUUUGGAUAAUGCCAUGAAUUCUAAUGUGACAGUAGUCUCUAGGGUAAACCAUGUUUUUUCUCAGGGUGUGCAGGUAAACCCAGGGCUCAUUCCAGGUCAAUCAACAGUUAACCACAGUCUGGGGACAGGAAAACCUGCAACUCAAACUGGGCCUCAAACAAGUCAGUCUGGUACCAGUAGCAUGUCUGGACCCCAACAGCUAAUGAUUCCUCAAACAUUAGCACAGCAGAAUAGAGAGAGGCCCCUUCUUCUAGAAGAACAGCCUCUACUUCUACAGGAUCUUUUGGAUCAAGAAAGGCAAGAACAGCAGCAGCAAAGACAGAUGCAAGCCAUGAUUCGUCAGCGAUCAGAACCGUUCUUCCCUAAUAUUGAUUUUGAUGCAAUUACAGAUCCUAUAAUGAAAGCCAAAAUGGUGGCCCUUAAAGGUAUAAAUAAAGUGAUGGCACAAAACAAUCUGGGCAUGCCACCAAUGGUGAUGAGCAGGUUCCCUUUUAUGGGCCAGGUGGUAACUGGAACACAGAACAGUGAAGGACAGAACCUUGGACCACAGGCCAUUCCUCAGGAUGGCAGUAUAACACAUCAGAUUUCUAGGCCUAAUCCUCCAAAUUUUGGUCCAGGCUUUGUCAAUGAUUCACAGCGUAAGCAGUAUGAAGAGUGGCUCCAGGAGACCCAACAGCUGCUUCAAAUGCAGCAGAAGUAUCUUGAAGAACAAAUUGGUGCUCACAGAAAAUCUAAGAAGGCCCUUUCAGCUAAACAACGUACUGCCAAGAAAGCUGGGCGUGAAUUUCCAGAGGAAGAUGCAGAACAACUCAAGCAUGUUACUGAACAGCAAAGCAUGGUUCAGAAACAGCUAGAACAGAUUCGUAAACAACAGAAAGAACAUGCUGAAUUGAUUGAAGAUUAUCGGAUCAAACAGCAGCAGCAAUGUGCAAUGGCCCCACCUACCAUGAUGCCCAGUGUCCAGCCCCAGCCACCCCUAAUUCCAGGUGCCACUCCACCCACCAUGAGCCAACCCACCUUUCCCAUGGUGCCACAGCAGCUUCAGCACCAGCAGCACACAACAGUUAUUUCUGGCCAUACUAGCCCUGUUAGAAUGCCCAGUUUACCUGGAUGGCAACCCAACAGUGCUCCUGCCCACCUGCCCCUCAAUCCUCCUAGAAUUCAGCCCCCAAUUGCCCAGUUACCAAUAAAAACUUGUACACCAGCCCCAGGGACAGUCUCAAAUGCAAAUCCACAGAGUGGACCACCACCUCGGGUAGAAUUUGAUGACAACAAUCCCUUUAGUGAAAGUUUUCAAGAACGGGAACGUAAGGAACGUUUACGAGAACAGCAAGAGAGACAACGGAUCCAACUCAUGCAGGAGGUAGAUAGACAAAGAGCUUUGCAGCAGAGGAUGGAAAUGGAGCAGCAUGGUAUGGUGGGCUCUGAGAUAAGUAGUAGUAGGACAUCUGUGUCCCAGAUUCCCUUCUACAGUUCCGACUUACCUUGUGAUUUUAUGCAACCUCUAGGACCCCUUCAGCAGUCUCCACAACACCAACAGCAAAUGGGGCAGGUUUUACAGCAGCAGAAUAUACAACAAGGAUCAAUUAAUUCACCCUCCACCCAAACUUUCAUGCAGACUAAUGAGCGAAGGCAGGUAGGCCCUCCUUCAUUUGUUCCUGAUUCACCAUCAAUCCCUGUUGGAAGCCCAAAUUUUUCUUCUGUGAAGCAGGGACAUGGAAAUCUUUCUGGGACCAGCUUCCAGCAGUCCCCAGUGAGGCCUUCUUUUACACCUGCUUUACCAGCAGCACCUCCAGUAGCUAAUAGCAGUCUCCCAUGUGGCCAAGAUUCUACUAUAACCCAUGGACACAGUUAUCCGGGAUCAACCCAAUCGCUCAUUCAGUUGUAUUCUGAUAUAAUCCCAGAGGAAAAAGGGAAAAAGAAAAGAACAAGAAAGAAGAAAAGAGAUGAUGAUGCAGAAUCCACCAAGGCUCCAUCAACUCCCCAUUCAGAUAUAACUGCCCCACCGACUCCAGGCAUCUCAGAAACUACCUCUACUCCUGCAGUGAGCACACCCAGUGAGCUUCCUCAACAAGCCGACCAAGAGUCGGUGGAACCAGUCGGCCCAUCCACUCCCAAUAUGGCAGCAGGCCAGCUAUGUACAGAAUUAGAGAACAAACUGCCCAAUAGUGAUUUCUCACAAGCAACUCCAAAUCAACAGACGUAUGCAAAUUCAGAAGUAGACAAGCUCUCCAUGGAAACCCCUGCCAAAACAGAAGAGAUAAAACUGGAAAAGGCUGAGACAGAGUCCUGCCCAGGCCAAGAGGAGCCUAAAUUGGAGGAACAGAAUGGUAGUAAGGUAGAAGGAAACGCUGUAGCCUGUCCUGUCUCCUCAGCACAGAGUCCUCCCCAUUCUGCUGGGGCCCCUGCUGCCAAAGGAGACUCAGGGAAUGAACUUCUGAAACACUUGUUGAAAAAUAAAAAGUCAUCUUCUCUUUUGAAUCAAAAACCUGAGGGCAGUAUUUGUUCAGAAGAUGACUGUACAAAGGAUAAUAAACUAGUUGAGAAGCAGAACCCAGCUGAAGGACUGCAAACUUUGGGGGCUCAAAUGCAAGGUGGUUUUGGAUGUGGCAACCAGUUGCCAAAAACAGAUGGAGGAAGUGAAACCAAGAAACAGCGAAGCAAACGGACUCAGAGGACGGGUGAGAAAGCAGCACCUCGCUCAAAGAAAAGGAAAAAGGACGAAGAGGAGAAACAAGCUAUGUACUCUAGCACUGACACGUUUACCCACUUGAAACAGCAGAAUAAUUUAAGUAAUCCUCCAACACCCCCUGCCUCUCUUCCUCCUACACCACCUCCUAUGGCUUGUCAGAAGAUGGCCAAUGGUUUUGCAACAACUGAAGAACUUGCUGGAAAAGCCGGAGUGUUAGUGAGCCAUGAAGUUACCAAAACUCUAGGACCUAAACCAUUUCAGCUGCCCUUCAGACCCCAGGACGACUUGUUGGCCCGAGCUCUUGCUCAGGGCCCCAAGACAGUUGAUGUGCCAGCCUCCCUCCCAACACCACCUCAUAACAAUCAGGAAGAAUUAAGGAUACAGGAUCACUGUGGUGAUCGAGAUACUCCUGACAGUUUUGUUCCCUCAUCCUCUCCUGAGAGUGUGGUUGGGGUAGAAGUGAGCAGGUAUCCAGAUCUGUCAUUGGUCAAGGAGGAGCCUCCAGAACCGGUGCCGUCCCCCAUCAUUCCAAUUCUUCCUAGCACUGCUGGGAAAAGUUCAGAAUCAAGAAGGAAUGACAUCAAAACUGAGCCAGGCACUUUAUAUUUUGCGUCACCUUUUGGUCCUUCCCCAAAUGGUCCCAGAUCAGGUCUUAUAUCUGUAGCAAUUACUCUGCAUCCUACAGCUGCUGAGAACAUUAGCAGUGUUGUGGCUGCAUUUUCCGACCUUCUUCACGUCCGAAUCCCUAACAGCUAUGAGGUUAGCAGUGCUCCAGAUGUCCCAUCCAUGGGUUUGGUCAGUAGCCACAGAAUCAACCCGGGUUUGGAGUAUCGACAGCAUUUACUUCUCCGUGGGCCUCCGCCAGGAUCUGCAAACCCUCCCAGAUUAGUGAGCUCUUACCGGCUGAAGCAGCCUAAUGUACCAUUUCCUCCAACAAGCAAUGGUCUUUCUGGAUAUAAGGAUUCUAGUCAUGGUAUUGCAGAAAGCGCAGCACUCAGACCACAGUGGUGUUGUCAUUGUAAAGUGGUUAUUCUUGGAAGUGGUGUGCGGAAAUCUUUCAAAGAUCUGACCCUUUUGAACAAGGAUUCCCGAGAAAGCACCAAGAGGGUAGAGAAGGACAUUGUCUUCUGUAGUAAUAACUGCUUUAUUCUUUAUUCAUCAACUGCACAAGCGAAAAACUCAGAAAACAAGGAAUCCAUUCCUUCAUUGCCACAAUCACCUAUGAGAGAAACGCCUUCCAAAGCAUUUCAUCAGUACAGCAACAACAUCUCCACUUUGGAUGUGCACUGUCUCCCCCAGCUCCCAGAGAAAGCUUCUCCCCCUGCCUCACCACCCAUCGCCUUCCCUCCUGCUUUUGAAGCAGCCCAAGUCGAGGCCAAGCCAGAUGAGCUGAAGGUGACAGUCAAGCUGAAGCCUCGGCUAAGAGCUGUCCAUGGUGGGUUUGAAGAUUGCAGGCCGCUCAAUAAAAAAUGGAGAGGAAUGAAAUGGAAGAAGUGGAGCAUUCAUAUUGUAAUCCCUAAGGGGACAUUUAAACCACCUUGUGAGGAUGAAAUAGAUGAAUUUCUAAAGAAAUUGGGCACUUCCCUUAAACCUGAUCCUGUGCCCAAAGACUAUCGGAAAUGUUGCUUUUGUCAUGAAGAAGGUGAUGGAUUGACAGAUGGACCAGCAAGGCUACUCAACCUUGACUUGGAUCUGUGGGUCCACUUGAACUGCGCUCUGUGGUCCACGGAGGUCUAUGAGACUCAGGCUGGUGCCUUAAUAAAUGUGGAGCUAGCUCUGAGGAGAGGCCUACAAAUGAAAUGUGUCUUCUGUCACAAGACGGGUGCCACUAGUGGAUGCCACAGAUUUCGAUGCACCAACAUUUAUCACUUCACUUGCGCCAUUAAAGCACAAUGCAUGUUUUUUAAGGACAAAACUAUGCUUUGCCCCAUGCACAAACCAAAGGGAAUUCAUGAGCAAGAAUUAAGUUACUUUGCAGUCUUCAGGAGGGUCUAUGUUCAGCGUGAUGAGGUGCGACAGAUUGCUAGCAUCGUGCAACGAGGAGAACGGGACCAUACCUUUCGCGUGGGUAGCCUCAUCUUCCACACAAUUGGUCAGCUGCUUCCACAGCAGAUGCAAGCAUUCCAUUCUCCUAAAGCACUCUUCCCUGUGGGCUAUGAAGCCAGCCGGCUGUACUGGAGCACUCGCUAUGCCAAUAGGCGCUGCCGCUACCUGUGCUCCAUUGAGGAGAAGGAUGGGCGCCCAGUGUUUGUCAUCAGGAUUGUGGAACAAGGCCAUGAAGACCUGGUUCUAAGUGACAUCUCACCUAAAGGUGUCUGGGAUAAGAUUUUGGAGCCUGUGGCAUGUGUGAGAAAAAAGUCUGAAAUGCUCCAGCUUUUCCCAGCGUAUUUAAAAGGAGAGGAUCUGUUUGGCCUGACCGUCUCUGCAGUGGCACGCAUAGCGGAAUCACUUCCUGGGGUUGAGGCAUGUGAAAAUUAUACCUUCCGAUACGGCCGAAAUCCUCUCAUGGAACUUCCUCUUGCCGUUAACCCCACAGGUUGUGCCCGUUCUGAACCUAAAAUGAGUGCCCAUGUCAAGAGGUUUGUGUUAAGGCCUCACACCUUAAACAGCACCAGCACCUCAAAGUCAUUUCAGAGCACAGUCACUGGAGAACUGAACGCACCUUAUAGUAAACAGUUUGUUCACUCCAAGUCAUCGCAGUACCGGAAGAUGAAAACUGAAUGGAAAUCCAAUGUGUAUCUGGCACGGUCUCGGAUUCAGGGGCUGGGCCUGUAUGCUGCUCGAGACAUUGAGAAACACACCAUGGUCAUUGAGUACAUCGGGACUAUCAUUCGAAACGAAGUAGCCAACAGGAAAGAGAAGCUUUAUGAGUCUCAGAACCGUGGUGUGUACAUGUUCCGCAUGGAUAACGACCAUGUGAUUGACGCGACGCUCACAGGAGGGCCCGCAAGGUAUAUCAACCAUUCGUGUGCACCUAAUUGUGUGGCUGAAGUGGUGACUUUUGAGAGAGGACACAAAAUUAUCAUCAGCUCCAGUCGGAGAAUCCAGAAAGGAGAAGAGCUCUGCUAUGACUAUAAGUUUGACUUUGAAGAUGACCAGCACAAGAUUCCGUGUCACUGUGGAGCUGUGAACUGCCGGAAGUGGAUGAACUGAAAUGCAUUCCUUGCUAGCUCAGCGGGCGGCUUGUCCCUAGGAAGAGGCGAUUCAACACACCAUUGGAAUUUUGCAGACAGAAAGAGAUUUUUGUUUUCUGUUUUAUGACUUUUUGAAAAAGCUUCUGGGAGUUCUGAUUUCCUCAGUCCUUUAGGUUAAAGCAGCGCCAGGAGGAAGCUGACAGAAGCAGCGUUCCUGAAGUGGCCGAGGUUAAACGGAAUCACAGAAUGGUCCAGCACUUUUGCUUUUUUUUCUUUUCCUUUUCUUUUUUUUUUGUUUGUUUUUUGUUUUGUUUUUCCCUUGUGGGUGGGUUUCAUUGUUUUGGUUUUCUAGUCUCACUAAGGAGAAACUUUUACUGGGGCAAAGAGCCGAUGGCUGCCCUGCCCCGGGCAGGGGCCUUCCUAUGAAUGUAAGACUGAAAUCACCAGCGAGGGGGACAGAGAGUGCUGGCCACGGCCUUAUUAAAAAGGGGCAGGCCCUCUAACUUCAAAAUGUUUUUAAAUAAAGUAGACACCACUGAACAAGGAAUGUACUGAAAUGACUUCCUUAGGGAUAGAGCUAAGGGAUAAUAACUUGCACUAAAUACAUUUAAAUACUUGAUUCCAUGAGUCAGUUUAUUGUAGUUUUUGAUUUCUGUAAAAUAAGAGAAACUUUUGUAUUUAUUAUUGAAUAAGUGAAUGAAGCUAUUUUUAAAUAAAGUUAGAAGAAAGCCAAGCUGCUGCUGUUACCUGCAGAACUAACAAACCCUGUUACUUUGUACAGAUAUGUAAAUAUUUUGAGAAAAAAUACAGUAUAAAAAUAGUUAUUGACCAAAUGCUACCAGGCUCUGCAGCAGCUCGGGGGCUUAUAAAAUGUUCAUAGGGAUGUUACAAUAUAAUUUUGUGUUAUAAAAUAUGCCAUUAUAAUUAUGUAAUAACCAAAAUUUCAACCUAGAGUGUUGGGGGUUUUUUGGAAACCGCAGUCUAUUAGUACUCAAUGGUUUUAUACACCUUACUUCUGACAGAGCGGGGCGUAUGCUACGACUACAACUUUUAUAGCUGUUUUGGUAAUUUAAACUAAUUUUUUCAUAUUAUAUUGUUGCAUCCCUACUUCUUCAGUCAGGUUUUUUUGUGCUUACAAUUUGUGAUAACUGUGAAUAACUGCUUAAAAAUACACCCAAAUGGAGGCUGAAUUUUUUCUUCAGCAAAAGUAGUUUUGAUUAGAACUUUGUUUCAGCCACAGAGAAUCAUGUAAACGUAAUAGGAUCAUGUAGCAGAAACUUAAAUCUAACCCUUUAGCCUUCUAUUUAACACAAAAAUUUGAAAAAGUUAAAAAAAAAAAGGAGAUGUGAUUAUGCUUACAGCUGCAGGACUCUGGCAAUAGGGUUUUUGGAAGAUGUAAUUUUAAAAUGUGUUUGUAUGAACUGUUUGUUUACAUUUCUUUAAUAAAAAAAACACUGUUUUGUGUUUGCUUGUAGAAACUUAAUCAGCAUUUUGAACCAGGUUAGCUUUUUAUUUUGUACUUAAAAUUCUGGUACUGACACUUCACAGGCUAAGUAUAAAAUGAAGUUUUGUGUGCACAAUUCAAGUGGACUGUAAACUGUUGGUAUAUUCAGUGAUGCAGUUCUGAACUUGUAUAUGGCAUGAUGUAUUUUUAUCUUACAGAAUAAAUCAAUUGUAUAUAUUUUUCUCUUGAUAAAUAGCUGUAUGAAAUUUGUUUCCUGAAUAUUUUUCUUCUCUUGUACAAUAUCCUGACAUCCUACCAGUAUUUGUCCUACCGGGUUUUUGUUGUUUUCUGUUCUGUAUAAUAGUAUCUAAUGUUGGCAAAAAUUGAAUUUUUUGAAGUAUACAGAGUGUUAUGGGUUUUGGAAUUUGUGGACACAGAUUUAGAAGAUCACCAUUUACAAAUAAAAUAUUUUACAUCUAUAA